GCCACUGCCGUCGGGUAAGGUCCCAGCACGGACAUGGCCUCGCGCGGCGCCCGCCCGGGCCCGAGUCCCCCGCGCCCCGCUUUGUAGCCCCCCGGCGGAGAGGCGGCCUCGACGGUGCGGACGGCGCAGACGGCCGGGCGGGCGGCAUGGAGGCGGCGCAUCUGCUCCCGGCCGCCGACGUGCUGCGCCACUUCUCGGUGACAGCCGAGGGCGGCCUGAGCCCGGCGCAGGUGACCGGCGCGCGGGAGCGCUACGGCCCCAACGAGCUCCCGAGUGAGGAAGGGAAGUCCCUGUGGGAGCUGGUGCUGGAACAGUUUGAGGACCUCCUGGUGCGCAUCCUGCUGCUGGCUGCCCUUGUCUCCUUUGUCCUGGCCUGGUUCGAGGAGGGCGAGGAGACCACGACCGCCUUCGUGGAGCCCCUGGUCAUCAUGCUGAUCCUCGUGGCCAACGCCAUUGUGGGCGUGUGGCAGGAACGCAACGCCGAGAGUGCCAUCGAGGCCCUGAAGGAGUAUGAGCCUGAGAUGGGCAAGGUGAUCCGCUCGGACCGCAAGGGCGUGCAGAGGAUCCGUGCCCGGGACAUCGUCCCAGGGGACAUUGUAGAAGUGGCAGUGGGGGACAAAGUGCCUGCUGACCUCCGCCUCAUCGAGAUCAAGUCCACCACGCUGCGAGUGGACCAGUCCAUCCUGACGGGUGAAUCUGUGUCCGUGACCAAGCACACAGAGGCCAUCCCAGACCCCAGAGCUGUGAACCAGGACAAGAAGAACAUGCUGUUUUCUGGCACCAAUAUCACAUCGGGCAAAGCGGUGGGUGUGGCCGUGGCCACCGGCCUGCACACGGAGCUGGGCAAGAUCCGGAGCCAGAUGGCGGCAGUCGAGCCCGAGCGGACGCCGCUGCAGCGCAAGCUGGACGAGUUUGGACGGCAGCUGUCCCACGCCAUCUCUGUGAUCUGCGUGGCCGUGUGGGUCAUCAACAUCGGCCACUUCGCCGACCCGGCCCACGGUGGCUCCUGGCUGCGUGGCGCUGUCUACUACUUCAAGAUCGCCGUGGCCCUGGCGGUGGCGGCCAUCCCCGAGGGCCUCCCGGCUGUCAUCACUACAUGCCUGGCACUGGGCACGCGGCGCAUGGCACGCAAGAACGCCAUCGUGCGAAGCCUGCCGUCCGUGGAGACCCUGGGCUGCACCUCAGUCAUCUGCUCCGACAAGACGGGCACGCUCACCACCAAUCAGAUGUCUGUCUGCCGGAUGUUCGUGGUAGCCGAGGCCGAUGCGGGCUCCUGCCUUUUGCACGAGUUCACCAUCUCGGGUACCACGUAUACCCCCGAGGGCGAAGUGCGGCAGGGGGAUCAGCCUGUGCGCUGCGGCCAGUUCGACGGGCUGGUGGAGCUGGCGACCAUCUGCGCCCUGUGCAACGACUCGGCUCUGGACUACAACGAGGCCAAGGGUGUGUAUGAGAAGGUGGGAGAGGCCACGGAGACAGCUCUGACUUGCCUGGUGGAGAAGAUGAACGUGUUCGACACCGACCUGCAGGCUCUGUCCCGGGUGGAGCGAGCUGGCGCCUGUAACACGGUCAUCAAGCAGCUGAUGCGGAAGGAGUUCACCCUGGAGUUCUCCCGAGACCGGAAAUCCAUGUCCGUGUACUGCACGCCCACCCGCCCUCACCCUACUGGCCAGGGCAGCAAGAUGUUUGUGAAGGGGGCUCCUGAGAGUGUGAUCGAGCGCUGUAGCUCAGUCCGCGUGGGGAGCCGCACAGCACCCCUGACCCCCACCUCCAGGGAGCAGAUCCUGGCAAAGAUCCGGGAUUGGGGCUCAGGCUCAGACACGCUGCGCUGCCUGGCACUGGCCACCCGGGACGCGCCCCCAAGGAAGGAGGACAUGGAGCUGGACGACUGCAGCAAGUUUGUGCAGUACGAGACGGACCUGACCUUCGUGGGCUGCGUAGGCAUGCUGGACCCGCCGCGACCUGAGGUGGCUGCCUGCAUCACACGCUGCUACCAGGCGGGCAUCCGCGUGGUCAUGAUCACGGGGGAUAACAAAGGCACUGCCGUGGCCAUCUGCCGCAGGCUUGGCAUCUUUGGGGACACGGAAGACGUGGCGGGCAAGGCCUACACGGGCCGCGAGUUUGAUGACCUCAGCCCCGAGCAGCAGCGCCAGGCCUGCCGCACCGCCCGCUGCUUCGCCCGCGUGGAGCCCGCACACAAGUCCCGCAUCGUGGAGAACCUGCAGUCCUUUAACGAGAUCACUGCUAUGACUGGCGAUGGAGUGAACGACGCACCAGCCCUGAAGAAAGCAGAGAUCGGCAUCGCCAUGGGCUCAGGCACGGCCGUGGCCAAGUCGGCGGCAGAGAUGGUGCUGUCAGAUGACAACUUUGCCUCCAUCGUGGCUGCGGUGGAGGAGGGCCGGGCCAUCUACAGCAACAUGAAGCAAUUCAUCCGCUACCUCAUCUCCUCCAAUGUUGGCGAGGUCGUCUGCAUCUUCCUCACGGCAAUUCUGGGCCUGCCCGAAGCCCUGAUCCCUGUGCAGCUGCUCUGGGUGAACCUGGUGACAGACGGCCUACCUGCCACGGCUCUGGGCUUCAACCCGCCAGACCUGGACAUCAUGGAGAAGCUGCCCCGGAGCCCCCGAGAAGCCCUCAUCAGUGGCUGGCUCUUCUUCCGAUACCUGGCUAUCGGAGUGUACGUAGGCCUGGCCACAGUGGCUGCCGCCACCUGGUGGUUUGUGUAUGACGCCGAGGGACCUCACAUCAACUUCUACCAGCUGAGGAACUUCCUGAAGUGCUCCGAAGACAACCCGCUCUUUGCCGGCAUCGACUGUGAGGUGUUCGAGUCACGCUUCCCCACCACCAUGGCCUUGUCCGUGCUCGUGACCAUUGAAAUGUGCAAUGCCCUCAACAGCGUCUCGGAGAACCAGUCGCUGCUGCGGAUGCCGCCCUGGAUGAACCCCUGGCUGCUGGUGGCUGUGGCCAUGUCCAUGGCCCUGCACUUCCUCAUCCUGCUCGUGCCGCCCCUGCCUCUCAUUUUCCAGGUGACCCCACUGAGCGGGCGCCAGUGGGUGGUGGUGCUCCAGAUAUCUCUGCCUGUCAUCCUGCUGGAUGAGGCCCUCAAGUACCUGUCCCGGAACCACAUGCACGCCUGUCUUUAUCCAGGCCUUCUCAGGACAGUCUCGCAGGCCUGGAGUAGGCAGCCGCUGACCACCUCUUGGACCCCAGACCACACCGGGUUGGCCUCUUUGGGCCAGGGACACAGCAUCGUCUCGCUGUCAGAGCUGCUCAGAGAGGGAGGAAGCAGGGAAGAAAUGAGCCAGAAGUGAGCGCUGGGAACAGAGUGGAGUCUCCGGUGUGUACCUCAGACUGAUGGUGCCCAUGUGUUCGCCUCCGCCCCCCACCCUUGCCACCACACUCGCCCACUUGCCCACCGGGUCCCGCCGGAUAAAUGACAGGCCCGAGGUCAGAAUGGCCAUCCCCGGGCCCCGUCCUGGGGUCUCUGUCCCCACUUCCUUCUGGCCUGGGAGGUCUGUAAUUCCUGUCUCCUGGACUCUCCUGGGAAGUUCCCUGCUCUGCAGCUCUGGCCCAGGAGCUGCAGGCUGGGAGGGGGCAGCCAAGAAGCCGGAGCUGGCAGCAUACCCAGAGAUCCGGGGCCCCCCCACCCCCAAAUCACGAGUGCAGCUGGAGCUUGCUCCCCCUUGUUCGGAAGCUGGACGUUCACUUGGUGACUGGUGCCUCUGCACUGACGGAGGACUCUGGGGGUCCUUCUUACCGGCUCUGACCUCUCUCUUCGUGCCUGGUCUGGGACUGGGUCAGCCCUGGGGGAUCAGAAGGGGCCAUCUGGGCCCAGCUGUGUACAGCGAGGGUGGGCAGCCCCCUCCACUCCACUCUGCUUCCACAAAGUCGGCUCCCGAGAGCUCGAGGCUGCUUCUGUUUAUAUGUGCAGGGCCCGGGCGGGUGAAGGGUCAGAGAGACGGACACAAGGAGCCGGCAGGAGGGCGGAGCGAGGAUGUCCUUUCCCGGGAGACAAGUCGGGAAAGCCUGGCUGGACUGCCUCAGCCCCGCGCGCCUCCUGGACUCAGGGUUCCCCGUCCUGAGCUCGGGAGAUGUUCAGAGUCACACUGCCGCCCGGUCUGCCACGCAGAGGUCCAACUUGCCACCCGCGUCCCUGGUACCUGAGACCACCGACAUCCUCAGGUUCCUGACCGUGGCGCCCUUCUACCCAGCCCAGUGUGCGGCCGCCGCGCUGUCUGCACAGCUGGGGGCCUCUGAGCCUGGUGGGCUUCCUGGACUCUUGGCCUCACUCCUUGCCCCCUCCCCACGACACCCAUGAGCCGAAAGGAUGUCACUAAGGAUGGCUGAUUCCCCAAGGGCACCCGCUCUCCCUCCCUCCCUGCUGGAGGAACACGUCAUAUCAGAUGAGAGGAAGAUGGCCUCUGAUGGACAGAAUUUUUCUCUUAACUCAGCUUUUGCUACUUUGGCAAAAACUAGCGAGGGGUAGCAGAAACCUGCACCAAGGAUUGUCCCUAUGUCUUGGCCACUCCUAGAGCGUGUGCAGACUGAUGAUUUUAUAUGUAAAUCAAGACUCACAUCCCUUUCCUAGUCCCCCACAUCCAAAGCCCCUCAGCCUGCCUUGCAGACCAAUGGGCUCCAUGUUCUGUAGCCCCCUCCCCUACGCCUCACCCCUCCUCCCUCUCACAGGUUCUGGGCGGCCAGUGAGAGAAACGCAGUGGGGGAGGCAGGGAGUCUGGUGCCUGCAGAGAUUCUCUGCUUCUUUCCUGGGGGGAGGUGGGGAGGUCUUAGCAGGAGCGGGCCCUGUACCCACCUGCUGACCUGCUGUUUGGUAGAGAAAUAAAGGUUGUGUGACUGGGGGAA